CCCUCCCCCACCCCUCCCCGUGCGAGUGUCUCCCUCUCCCUCUCGCUCUCUCUCUCUCUCCCUCUCUCUCUCUCUUUUGUGAGUUAUAGCAACCGUUGCCUUGUGAAUCAAGCGCCAUAGUCACCGUAGUCCUGGCGACUGUUACCCAUCAACAACAACUACUCCUCUCCUCCUCCUCCUCCUCUUCCUCCUCCUCCUCCCCACCACCACCAUCUCCAUCACCCACCAACAACACCACAAUAAUCCACAGCCAAGGUGAAUAUUCUUCGGUCUCUACAUGUGUGUGGGAGCGUGUGGCUGCGUGUGAACGCGUGUGUCCGUGCGUGUGUGUGUUCGUGUGUGCGAGCCGAGUGUGGCUGUGCUGGGGUCUCACUCCUGACACGGGGGCUGCCGCUGCGGCGCCGCCGCCGAGGGGCUCUGUUCCCCGGGCUUGUUUACAAUGGACCCUGCGCGCCGCGGCUGGGUCGGGGGUGUGGGCGCCGCGCCGCCCGCCGGCCCCGGCCCUGCGCCGGCCGCACUUCAGGGAUGGAGCGGGAGCUUGGGGGGCUGCGAGCCGAGCGGGAGAGGGAGCCACAGUUUUCCGAUGCGGAUGCUGGAUCUUUCCCUUAGGUCUGGUCUGAGGAGGAGGGUCAGGUGAAGAGAUAAGAAUUUGUUCUUUCUUUAAUUUUCUUCUUUUCCAACGCUGCUGUUUCCUGCUUCUUUCAAAGCCGAAAUAGACAACAGUGUGCAAGGGGGGGACCCAAGAGGUGGUGUUUUGUUGUUGUUGUUGUUCACUUGUGGGGCCUUGUUAUGGGUUUUGUUAUUUUUAAUCCUCAUACGUUGGUGAACUUUUCCCACCGCCCAUUCCCUUCAUUUUUGCCCCUCUUUGCCUGGUGCUGAAUGGGCUGCUCUUCUUUCACCAUCAUCAGCUUCAUGGUUUUCUUUUUUCUUUUUAAAACUGUAUUUUCUUUGUGCGGCAAACAGUCUUAACAUCCAUUCAGCACUCUUCCCUCCCCCUCUUUCUCCCCCCCCCCACACACCCCUUGCACACAUAUUGAAACCUGGGGCCUGUUCGUUGGGCCCUCUUUGCUGUACUGGGAAAGAUGUUUUUCUUUUUUAAAGUCUGUCUCCUCUCUCUUCUUUGGUGUGUGUGUGUGUGUGUGUGUGUGUGUGUGUGUGUGUGUGUGUGUGUGUGCUUGUGAUUUAAACCGGAUGCAGGGCAUCUGUGAUACUUGGGUUAGUAGUUAUUGACAGUGCUUUAUCCUUCAUGUGGAGGUGGGAGGGGGAGUAGUGAGGUUCCGUUUCACUUUGAUGAUCCUCCUUCCCCGCAGUAGAGUGUUAACAAUUUUCAUUGUGAUUAUGAGACUUUGUGAUGAACAGGGAAGGGACACAAGGAAGCUUUGUGAGAACUCAGUUCACAGUGUUAUUUGUGACAGUUAUGGUACUUUAAGAGUUUUUUUUUUUUUAAUCUCCUCAUUUUCCUUUGAGAGUUGAAAUUCAAGUCAAGUUCAUAAAGAAUGUAUGAAGGUUCUCAACUUGAAACGUGUGUAUAUUUCACUUUCUUUCUGGUUAAGAUCUAGGCAUGUGUGUACUUAACAUAUUCUUUUUAUUUACUUUUUGAUUUUCUUUGGACAGUGACUUGAACCUGCUCAGGAGAGAGAACUUUUUCCUUUUUAAGUAUUUCUUUUAAAAAUUAUUUUUCUCUGUAGAUUUGAAUACUUAUUAGUCCUUAUAUAGUAGGUUCUUGGUUAACGUUAACCCAGUUUUACAGAUCCCCUAAAUUUGUUCAUUUUUUUCAGCUUAACUUUUAGUUAAUAGAUUUAUCAGUAGAGUUUUGAUAAUGAAUGUGUGCUAAAACAAAUAUAAUGUACUAUUGUAGUUGCACAUAUUGAAGUUUUAAAUUUACAGUUUUAAAAUGCUUAUUCAAAUAGUCUUCUUUCUAACAGCAAACAUAUAUUGAUUUAACUGACACAGCAGCUUGUGAAUAAUGUGACAGUACUAAUUAUUCUUGAGAUUGUCAACGAGCAGGGUGGGUAAUUAUAAUGCUAUUAAGGCUAAUAUUUUGUAAAAUAAGAGUUGGGAUUUUAAAAAAACUUUUUCAAUUCAUUUCCUUGUGAUUGCUAUUUUAAAUGAAGACGAUAUUUUGUUCUGAAAGAAGUCUUUCUCAGAGCACUCAGAUUUGUUUAUAAUUAUUCCUCCUCUCCCCAAACUGGGUUCCAUGCAAAUCUCUAAUACUAACUUGUAUUUUUUUUUCUGUUCAGAUGAGUGUCAAAUGCCUGAACACUUUUGGAUGGUGAAGCUCCUGGGUCCUAUAAACUCUCUCUGAAGUUAAUAGGAGUUUUGCUGUCUUGGGACAGUUUCAGACCUUAUGCCAUUUACAUAAUAGGUUUUCAGCCACUUGGUCAUUCUGGCAUUUUAUGGUAGAGAAUACGUUGAGUUUGGCUCUGGAAGGAAUAUGAGGUAAUUUGAACACAUGUUCUUUAUAAAUAAUGAACUGUGUGUACAUAAUACAGAGUAUUUUCAGAUGUCAUAUAUGGAGUCUCAUGUCUGAAUUUUUUCAAUAGUAAUUUUCUUUUUUCAUAUUUUGAUGUUUUUCCUUUCUUGAUGGUUGGCAAUAGUUAAUAUGGUGAAGAACUUUAUUUUCUAUCACUACUAUAUAUGUUUUCAAGAAAACAGUAUUAUUUACAUAGUUAUGUGUUUUCAGUUUAUAUUUUUAAAUGCUUCAGUUAACCUAGCUUUCGGUGGUGCUGUAAAAACCAGAAGAGAAUUCCUUCCUUUCCACCUACCAACUUCCCAUCCCAACCAAUCCUGCCCCAGGUAGGAUUAAGGUCAUGCUGCAUUUAAAAGUCAUAACUGCCACACAGAGUUUUAUAGAGGAACAAUAAAGAAAGAGCACUGGAACUCCAAUAAUGUAAAAUUUUCAGGCACUACUCAGAGUGCUUUGAGAGCACAAAUAUGAGACUCAUAGGUUAGUCUUUUCCUGUCCUUUGAUACCCAUAUGUGACCCUGUGUGAUGUAUGGGUUUGUCAUUCUAAAAUGGCAGUCAAAUAAGUGUAUAUGCCACAUAUAUUUUCAUAGUGGUUUCAUAGACUAAACAUUAAGCCUAUAUCAAAGGAAGUUUCAAUUAAAGGUAGAAAAAUAAUAGUUGACUUUAUGAAAUUAAGCCAAUGAUACAGUAGCAGGCUUAUCAGUAGAUAUUAAGUAUUUGGUAGAGUAAUUGGUUAAUAUACUGCUGAUGUCAUAAUUCCCCUACUCUACUACUCAAUAAUAGUUUUGUUAUGUAGGAAGAUGCAGCAGCUUGUUUGUGUGAACUUCUGCUUCCACUACAAACAGUACUUUAAAGACAGGCCUUCCACUGCCAUUCAGAAAGAGACCAUCAUGCAGACAUCAGAGACUGGGUCGGACACAGGCUCGACAGUGACCUUACAAACAUCUGUGGCUAGUCAAGCAGCAGUGCCUACGCAGGUGGUACAGCAAGUACCAGUACAACAACAGGUACAGCAGGUACAGACUGUGCAGCAGGUACAACAUGUCUAUCCCGCUCAGGUGCAGUAUGUGGAAGGAAGCGAUACUGUCUAUACCAAUGGAGCAAUCCGAACAACAACGUAUCCUUACACAGAGACACAGAUGUACAGCCAAAAUACUGGAGGGAAUUACUUUGAUACUCAAGGGAGUUCCGCCCAGGUGACUACCGUGGUCUCAUCCCACAGUAUGGUGGGCACUGGUGGGAUUCAGAUGGGCGUCACAGGAGGACAACUCAUCAGCAGCUCUGGAGGAACCUAUCUGAUCGGCAACUCAAUGGAGAAUUCUGGUCACUCAGUGACACACACAACUCGGGCCUCCCCAGCGACAAUUGAAAUGGCGAUUGAGACGCUGCAAAAGUCUGACGGUCUGUCCACUCACAGAAGCUCUCUUCUCAACAGCCAUCUCCAGUGGCUGUUGGACAAUUAUGAGACAGCAGAAGGAGUGAGCCUUCCCAGAAGCACUCUGUACAACCACUACCUUCGACACUGUCAGGAACACAAACUGGACCCAGUCAAUGCUGCCUCUUUUGGAAAAUUAAUAAGAUCAAUUUUUAUGGGGCUACGAACCAGGAGAUUGGGCACUAGAGGAAACUCCAAAUACCACUACUAUGGGAUUCGUGUCAAGCCAGAUUCCCCUCUUAAUCGUCUGCAAGAAGACAUGCAGUAUAUGGCUAUGAGACAACAACCCAUGCAACAGAAACAAAGGUACAAGCCUAUGCAGAAAGUGGAUGGGGUUGCAGAUGGUUUCACAGGAAGUGGUCAACAGACAGGCACAUCUGUUGAGCAAACUGUAAUUGCCCAAAGCCAACAUCAUCAACAGUUUUUAGAUGCAUCUCGAGCACUUCCAGAGUUUGGAGAAGUUGAAAUCUCUUCUCUGCCAGAUGGUACUACCUUUGAGGAUAUCAAGUCACUGCAGAGUCUUUAUAGAGAGCACUGUGAGGCAAUAUUGGACGUUGUUGUGAAUCUUCAAUUUAGCCUGAUAGAAAAAUUGUGGCAAACAUUCUGGCGCUAUUCUCCCUCUACUCCAACUGAUGGCACUACCAUUACCGAAUCGAGCAAUCUGAGUGAAAUAGAAAGUCGACUUCCGAAAGCAAAGCUGAUAACUCUGUGCAAACAUGAGUCUAUCCUGAAAUGGAUGUGUAACUGUGACCAUGGGAUGUACCAGGCUUUGGUGGAGAUUCUCAUCCCCGACGUCCUUAGACCUAUUCCUAGUGCCUUGACCCAAGCCAUUCGAAAUUUUGCAAAAAGCCUUGAAGGUUGGCUUUCCAAUGCCAUGAACAAUAUUCCACAGAGAAUGAUACAAACCAAGGUUGCCGCUGUAAGUGCCUUUGCCCAGACUCUGCGAAGAUACACGUCGCUUAAUCACCUGGCCCAGGCAGCUCGUGCAGUGCUUCAGAACACUUCCCAAAUCAACCAGAUGCUUAGUGACCUCAACCGUGUCGACUUUGCCAAUGUCCAGGAGCAGGCUUCCUGGGUGUGCCAGUGUGAUGACAACAUGGUUCAGAGACUAGAAACAGACUUCAAGAUGACUCUUCAGCAGCAGAGCACCCUGGAGCAGUGGGCUGCGUGGCUUGACAAUGUGAUGAUGCAAGCACUGAAACCCUAUGAAGGAAGACCCAGUUUUCCUAAAGCCGCCAGGCAGUUUCUGCUAAAAUGGUCUUUCUACAGCUCAAUGGUUAUUCGGGACUUAACCUUACGCAGUGCUGCUAGCUUUGGCUCCUUCCACCUGAUCCGUCUACUCUACGACGAAUAUAUGUUUUACUUAGUAGAACAUCGUGUUGCUCAGGCAACAGGAGAGACUCCUAUAGCAGUCAUGGGCGAGACAAACCUUGUAGAUGAAAAAAAUACUCCUAUCAUGGAACUCUUUAUAAGCAAACUUCUGAAUUUUGGUGAUUUAAAUGCCGUGUCUCCUGGAAAUCUGGAUAAAGAUGAAGGCAGUGAAGUAGAAAGUGAAAUGGAUGAAGAACUGGAUGACUCUUCAGAGCCUCAAGCCAAAAGAGAGAAAACAGAGCUGAGCCAGGCAUUUCCAGUGGGCUGCAUGCAGCCUGUUCUCGAGACUGGCGUGCAACCAAGCCUCCUGAAUCCAAUUCACAGCGAGCACAUUGUCACAAGUACUCAGACUAUCAGACAGUGCAGCGCUACAGGAAAUACCUACACUGCAGUCUAAAGAAUAUUAAAGCGUAUUUUUCCAGCUUACAUUAACCCUGUUGAUAUUGGGCUUAAGUUGAAAAUUUAAUAAGCCUGAAGGUCGACUGUUGUCAAAUUCUAUCUGUGCUGAACAUUAACUUUUUGGAGUUGUGAAAUGGAAUGGGUGUAUGUAUUUUGCCAGAUCUUUUUUUUUAACGUAAACAAAUUAUUUGCUUCUUAAUAAUGAAUUUUUUCCCUUAGUUUCAGGUGUCAAGAAGGAUUUUUACAACACUUAAUGUCAAUGUUUUGUUUUCUUAUAAUUAAAAAGUAAUUUACAUUUUUUGUAGCUUAAAAUAUUUUAUUGUUGAUUGUUAGUCUUGGUGUAUGAUUUCAUGUGUAAGUUUUUUAAUUAGAUGCACUUCUGUGAAAUAUCAAAAGAAAUGAUUUUUUUGAUUUACACUGGAGGCAUGCCCAUUUGGCAGCAGAUGCAUCAAAUUUGCUUUUGAAAGGUGCUUUUCAUUGGACAGAACCAUAAGACACUAUUUUGAUAACAUUUUGAGUAUGGAGAGAGAAUACAGAGCAUUUUUAUUAUAGUGCUAGAGGGUUUGGAAGGUCAUCUAUUUUUCUCUGAGGAAAAAAUGAGCUGUACAUUUAUCAGUUCAGAGUAAAUGACAGAAUUGCAAGAGAUUAUGCUAAUAUGUACAUAAUUUGUGUACAUAAUUAUUAAACCAUGUUAACAAUGCAAGCUUCCGUUAAACAUUGAAUUUUAACUAUUAUUUGCAUACCAAUUCCUCUGUUUAAAGACUACUGAUUCUGUAUUUGGGACCACUGCACAGAUGCAUUCUGCUGUUAAGUGGGGGCUGUUAUAGUUAGAUACUGAAGCAGAAAAAAAAGACUUGACUUUUUUUUUUUAAGUGUACAUGCUACUUAUGCUGAGCUGGACAUACAGGAAACCAUUCCAUUUGGAUGACUUUCUUUUAUUCCAGGUCUUUUUCCUAAUAGUAGUUCAAUAUGCUGCUAUUAUAAACGAGAAUUUAUAGAAUGCAAGGAAUGUAGCAACCUACAUAACGUUAUUUCCUUCAAAACUAUUUCCUGGUUUCUAAAGUAUGUGGAUUUAAAUUGUAAACAGAACCUGAAGGCAGUGUAACUGGCACACCUCACUGUUACUUAUCCCCAAUUCUGUAGGAUUUGGAUAGGUGGCUGGAUGGACCAUUGCCAUUGAAGAAUGUACAUCAGGGAUCAUCGUACCUCGGCUAUUACAUGGUGCCUUAAAACAGAACUGAAGCUAAGGUUUAGUAAGGUUUAUUUUGUUCAUGUGACUAACUCUUCAAUCCAUUUGACAAAGUGUGCCUGUCAUUUUCAGAUUCCUGAAGUAAGGACAGGUGACAUGUUCUUCAAAGGAAAUUUAGGGAAAACAAAGGAAAACAAAAAGACAAAAAUCAGUUUCCCUCUUUGAGUGACCGUGGAUCUAUUUUUUAUUCUUAGAGCUGAAUAUUACUUGAUUACAAAUCAGAUUGCUUAAGGGUGUGGAAUAGCAGGCUAGUUUUAAUACCAACUUGUUAACAUAAAAUCAUAUAUGUUUUAGACCAUUCUUAUUUAGUUACAAUUUUAGAAAGUUAACAAAGUAAGCAGGUACUUAUCGAAGUGCAUCUUUUCAGUCUAAAUGUUUGUCUGUGUGUCUAGGUGCUGGUGAGUCCACAUGGACACAUGAGUGCCCAUGGGGCAGGAGUCUGCUAUAAAGUCAGAAGGUGAGAUCCUAGAGAGUUACACCCAGCCCCAUUUUAAUUUGCAUGAAAAGCCAAGGUUCUUUUAAGCACUCAAAUUAUUUAAUGAUUAAAACACAAGAAAGGCACAUCUGUUCAUUUAAAUAGUUGUAAAAAACUAAUCAGCAAAAAUAAAUAGAUAAUAAAGCCAAAAAAAAGGAAAGCACAAAAUGAUUGACAGAUUAUCAAAUGAGGCCUAUAUUAAACCCAAGAUGUUUAUCUUUCCAGUGGUAUUGGGGUAAGGGGGGUGGGGGGUUGGAAAGACGAGGUGAGCCAGUCUGUAAAGUUAGAAAUACCAAAUGGCUUAUCGGGUAAUACACAGUGUAUUUAAGCUGUUGUUGCUUAAUUGCCUCAGACUACUCAAAUAACAUCAACAACAUUUCUUAAGUAAAAUUUAAAUAUUUUAGAUGUAAUUUUAAAAACUGAUCCAAAUUUUUUAUUAUACAACUCACUCAUAUAUUUGAAAGUCUUCACUAGCAUAGUAGCAUCACCUUCAUCUAAAUGUCAUUUAAAUUACUGUCCCCCUUUUUCCUCCCAAAAAGACAAUGGAUUUGUACCAAAACACACACAAAAAAGGCAAACAAAACAUGAUAAUCUGCAAAAGUUCAUGUAUCUACUUCAUUGUGCAUAGGAAGUGUUUACAGGUAAAAUUAAAAUCAAAAAUUGAAAAAACACUCUUCAUUUUGGCUCUCCUUUCUGAAUUUUUUCAGUUUCCUGUCUCUACCCGCCAUCCUUUGAGUGAUACUAUAUCUGUAUUGGACCAAAUGUAUUUACUGGUUUCAUUUUGUUUAUUGAAUGACUUUAAAUGUAUUUAUUAUCAUUGUUUAAUUUAAUGUUGGAUAUAUUUGUAUCAUUACAGGAAUCUGGUAAUAAUGGGCAAAUUUAGAUUGAUGAGGCUUAGGGAUCGGGGAUGCUCCAGGAUUCAACAUUUCUUCCAAUUGUUCAUGGUUUGUUCUAAAUUAGGACAGAUUAAGAACUAAUAAAACAUUAUUACAUUUGAACUUGACUCAAUAAAAAUAUUCUGAUCUCCUUUAUGAAUAUUAGGAAUAUUCUUUGUGAUUAGUGUAAGUAGUUUGGAUCAAAACAUAAAAAGAAGACCUAUGGUUUAUGCUACUUCUAGUUAUUUGUAGUUCACAGUAAAACAUGCACAGACAUACACACAAACAUUUUCAUCAAUUUCGAAUUUGAAUUGUGAAAAAUAUAUAAGAAAAUAAAAACAAUUUAUACAUUUGAGCAAAUUGAGCAAUCACAUUUAUUGCAUUUAUUUCCCUUUUUCCCUUUUUUCACUCAUUGAAAGUGUGGGUUUUCUAAAUAAUAUUAGACACUAACACUCAACAGAUUUAUUCACAAAUGACACAAGUACACAUUUUAAGACUUCUUUGUAUUUCUUGCAAUUAUAACCAAUCACUAGUCAUGAAAUAUACCUACAUAAACCAAGUCCUACACUUUCAGUGAGGAAGAAUGUAAGGAAGGUAUGUUGACUGUUUUCAAGUUUCAGAAAAGAUAUUUUCAUAUGAUAGGAUUGAGUAUCAUGGGUAUAGUUUGAUCUUGACAUAUAGUUUGAAAAUCAUACUCAAAAGAUUUGCAUUCAUGAAACCAGUGAACAAUAGGGUGGAAUGGAUGAACCAUCUCCUUGGAAGACAGGGCCCAAUUUUCAAUUUUUUCUUUGGCUAUCAAGUUGCUAGUCACUUAUUCAGGAUUUUCAUCCAAACUGUGUUUGGACUGACUGUAUAAGUCUUACUGCCUUUUCAGAAAUCUGCUUUCCUUUGUGUGAUUUUUCUUGUACUGUAUAGCACGGUUUAUGCACCUCUCUUUAGAUGGUGUACUUUAAAAACAAAAGUAAAAUUUAGAAAAUGGUUUUAACACUGCAUACCUAAAAUUAGUAGUGUGCAGCAUUGACUGCCUUUGAUUUGUAGUAGACAAGUAAAAAUGAAUACGUUCUUGUAGAAUGCUGUAAAAGUUAUUCAGGAAUGAAUACGGUUUUAGUGCCGUAAUCAUGAAUCUUUUUAUAUGAAUGCACUGUCUAAAAGUGCUAAAUGCAUUUUCAAAUUUUUAAAAAUUCCUCAGAUGAUAUAUUUGAAAUGUCUAAAAUAAUGCUGUGCUUGAAACAUUAGUGUAAAAGGAAAAAAAAAAUAGUGUCACUGUGAUGUUGGUCCUCCCUGUGUGGACACAAGUAGAAAGAAAAAACUUGGCAAGUCACCUUUGUGUACAAUUUGAGGCAGUGGUUAUAUACAAUAAAUUGACCUUUAUUAUAUCCCCCAGACACACACAUUCUUGGUGAGAAAAGAACAACCAUCCAGAAAUUGAGAUGAGAACUUUUGUGAUCUGUAUGAAUCACAGCAGAUCAUGGGGGAGGAGGAUUGGCAUGCAGUGCUGUUGAAAAUUGGGCUUGUUGUUAGAUCAGAACAACCUCCAUGUAUAUGGUUAGAACGAAUCAAUUAAUGGAAUCCUAGUAUUUCUGCAAGUUUGGUGAUUUUUAAAAACUGGAAUAGAAGCAUUAAUUCAGUGCUUAGUUCUAGUAUUAGAAAACCCCUUUGAUGUAAUGCCUUGUAUUAACCCUUUGAGCAUUGUAAGAUAUACAAUGGGGGACAAAAGCCUUUCAGAUCAUUUAUUUAGACUUAGACCGGUAAAGUAUACUCUAUAUCCAAAUGUCUAAUUAUGCUGUUUUUUUAAAGGGGGGGGUAGGAAGAGAAAGUGUUUCCACGCCGAACACUUGCAUUUUAUAUACAACUCUUAAUUUUUCUUCAAGAGGGCUUGAUAUAUUUAUUCCCAAAUAUUCACUGCCAUCUAAGUAAGUGUACUGUUUACAGAAAAAAAAAAUCAACUUUUCUAGUAUCACACCAUAGUCUCUAGAAAAGGAGGACAAAUACAUGGGCCUGGAUAGACCUAUGUCAUAACUGAUUUCUGCACAUUGAAGGUACCUAGAUUGCCUUUAAAAGGUAUAAAGAAAGGGUUAAGUUUCUUUUUUUUUUGUCUUUUUUUUCCCAAAAUGAAUCAAAAGAUCUCAUUUAUUUAGCUUUAGAAAGUACAAGUGUAAGUAAAGCCUUAGGAAGAAAGGAGUUCGAGUGGAUUAAGAGAAUCUGAACUCUUUGGGGGCAGUUAGGCUAUUUGGAGUUAGAUCGCUCAUAAAAUAUUGUUUGCGAAUUUCACACAGGGCAUAAUUUUAUCUAUGCUCCAAAACUUUAAUACGUUGUCAAAAAAUUAUAUAUAGAUAGAAUGGAGAGCAAAGCACUUGAUUUUAAGCUCAUCUGUCAGGAGAUGCUAUGACUACUGCUUCUGAUAUCUCUAAAUGUCAGUCUGCUUACACCAUUGCUGAUUUUGUUCAAGGGAAUCUCUUCGUGCACUUGAUUCCCUCUGUUCCCUGCGUGAUCGAACAUGAAAGCAGUGUUGUCUGCAGAUGUGCUUGCGCUGCCCUAGCUGGGUGCAAAUAAGAGUGUAACCUAUUCUGAUGUCUGGUGAAAGGACAUCCAUAGCAUAGUGCAAGUAUGCCGUAAACGUUGCUUUUUAGGCAGUUUAGGAAGUCAGACCAUGCAAAUUACUCAUGUGUUAACAUGCAAUACUCAAAGGGUUUUAAUUUAACUCUCUUCUUUUGAAUUCUUCAUGAUGAUUUACUGUAAAUGCUUCUCAGUUUGCAUGCCUUGAUCAUUGCUGCUAGUGAUUUUAUGUGCCAGUAGACCUGAGUUUAGUUUACCAAUUUUACUUAAAUAGUAAAAGCCACUUACAAAGUGACUGCCUAGGAUUUUUUUUUCCUUUCAUUUGAAAUAAUUGAUAAUAUGUUUUUUUAAAAAGAAAAAUGUGUUUUGUCUCUUCUUUUAUUUGGUUCUGGUUUGAUUCUUUUUCUCCCCUCUUUCCUUUGUUUUUUUUUUUUAAAUAAAUUAUGAUGUUGGGAUUGGAAGCCCUGAGUAAUGAAAAUCUUUGGUAAGAAUUGUUUAUGUAGCUCAAUAACGAGGACAACAAAUAUUCUUUAGAAGAAUUUUGAUUCUGGGGAGGAAAGAAAAUAUAAAAACUCCCAUUGACUGUUGAUAACCAAGUAAAUUUUUCCUUCAGUAAAUUAGUAUUUUUGAAGAAACGAUCGCCUUGUUUUAACUUGCUAAACAACAAUUUUAAAUGACCCAAUAAAGAAUCUAUUGAACUUUAUUCGUUUAAAAAGCAUCUUUUGUACCAAAGCAAAUUUUUUUCUCUACUCAUUUCCAUCAUCAAUUUGGACCUAUGGUGGUGACCAAUGCAUUGGUUACAGAAACUUUAAGUGAGUGCCUUGAGAAAACUUGGAAAUUUGUGCCUGAGGUGGUAAACUUUUAAUUAGGUUAAUUGUAGUGCUUACCAAUCAGUAACUUCACUAUCACUCAGGGCUUUCGUACCUUCUAGGUAAAACUUCUUUCAUUGUGUUUUUUUAAGAUACUGUAUUUUUUUUUAAGUGCCAUCAUUUAAAUUUCACUUAGUAAGUGGCAGAUUACAUUAUUCAGUCCCACAAGCACAGAAACAUAGUAACACUAGGAGAUAUUUGAACAUUUAUUUUACAAUCGACUGAAUAUAUUAUGUAAAUGAGGUAAGCAACUUUUGUAGAGAUUGUAUGUGUGAGAUAAUGUAAUGUUCUUUUCCAGUUUUUGGACUACAGUUGAAUAAACUUUUUAAUUAUUUAAAAACAUCUUUACCGAAUAACAUGUGAUGGUUUUUUGUAUAAUGUAUUUGAUUUUGUAAAUACGUAUUUCCUGAUGUGAUUUUUGUGAGAAAUGCUAAAUCUUUUAGUAUAUCAUGUCCUCUCAAAAUUGGCAGGAGCUAAAUAAUAGUUUGUGGGCGAUUUGUAUUGUGUACUGUACAAUAACUGGGGAACUUUUAUAAUUAUAAAAAUAUAUAUUAACUUUUAGUGUGUUGUUUAAACAAAUGACUGGAACAUACUAAAGAUAUUAGUAGGAUUUUUCUGAAUAUUUCAGACUUGAACUCAGGCUAGCUUUCUUGUGUUUUUCAAAACAAAAUGGUGUCUUGUCUUUUAAAAUCAAUAAAUUUGUUUCCUUGUUACAAAUA